GUCACAGAAAAUUUUAAGUUUUAAGAGAAACUCCUACAGUGAUUGGCAUCAAAGUAGGUAGUGUUCCCUCCCUCCCACCAAACAAAAGAAGUCCCUUAUCACCUGAGGAAUGCCCACUAAAUAAUAAGUAAAUAUUUAAUUACAUGGCUGGCUGGCUAUAUUAAGCUGUUUUGUUUUUAGGGGAAAAUGGUGUUACUUCUAACACAGAAAGAGUGCUGAAUUAAAAUCUUUCUCUGCAGCAAUAUCUAUUGAGAGGUGCUGACUGUUUUGCUACAGCAUGCAACUCAAAAGUGGCUGAAAAUAUGCAGCUUUGGGAGUCUACAGAUCAUUGCAGGAGCUAAAGGUCUAGUCAUUUUUUUUUAACCAAAGGUAAUCUGCAGCAGCUGGUAACCGUGGAGGUCUCUGCACAGGUUUGUGCCAAGAAUAUGCCUGUGUGAAGGGUUAUUGUGAGUAUAGGAUUAAGGUCUUUUUAUUUUGUAGUAGGCUAAAUUUGAUGCAAACCAGCAAGAUGGGAAAUGAGACAUGAAGAUGCAAUAAUGUAUUAUGCUUUUAGUGAACUUCCGAAGCUUAGAUUUGUUAGUGAGAUAUUGGUAUUUCAAUUUUAUUAGGUAAAUGUUGAAAAUAUAUCAAAAUCCAGUAUUUGUAAAGCAUUUAAUAAUAUUUUUUGAAGUUUAAUUUUCCCUUAUUUGCUUCAACCAACCAGAUAUCUUUCAAUGAGAUUUUUCCUCAAGAAUGAAAUAUCUUUUUAAGAAAAUUAUAUGAGAAUUGCUAAACAACUUGAUUAUCUCUAUUAAAAACAAGUUGAAAAGUGUGAACAUUUUAUCCCUAUUACGAGAAGCUUUGAAUUUGAAUUUUAAAAAUUGUUAUUGCUUUAUGAGAUAUUUAGGUCUCAAAUGUUAUAAUUAUAACCUCCACUUACUUAAAGACAAAAUAUUUACAAAACAAAGCUUGAUCUAAAGCCAUAGCUCCGUCUAGGAUUCAAUCACAGAAGAAUUAAUUGGUGUUUUUUAGGAUACACGGUCCUUUAUGACCUUUAUCAUAGUUAGAAGAUGAGGAAUUGGGCGCAGGGGCUCACGCCUGUAAUCCCAGCACUUUGGGAUGCUGAGGCGGGCAGAUGACGAGGUCAGGAGUUCGAGAACAGCCUGACCAACAUGGUGAAACCCUGUCUCUACUAAAAAUACAAAAAGUAGCCAGACGUGGUGGCACAUGCCUGUGCAUGUGCUGGGAUUACCCAGCUACUCAGGAGGCUGAGGCAGGAGGAUUGCUUGAACCUGGGAGGCAGAGGUUGCAGUGAGUCGAGAUCACGCCACUGUACUCCAGCCUGGGUGACAGAGCGAGACUCCGUCUCAAAAAAAAAAAAAAAAAAAAGCGCUGGGUGCAGUGGCUCACACCUAUAAUCCCAGCACUUUGGGAGGCCGAGGUGGGUGGAUCACAGGGUCAGGAGAUAGACCAUUCUGGCUAACACGGUGAAACCCCAUGUCUACUAAAAAUACAAAACUUAGCCGGGUGUGGUGGCACACGCCUGUAGUCCCAGCUACUCAGGAGGCUGAGGCAGGAGAAUCGCUUGAACCCAAGAUCGUGCCACUGCACUCCAGCCUGGGUGACAGAGCGAGACUCGAUCUCCAAAAACAAACAAACAAAAAAAGAUGAGGGAUCAGAUGGGAGAAUGACUUUAAGCUAUAUAGAAGGCAGAAUGCAUGCAUCAUAGACUUAAAACAUGUUGUUACUGUUGUGGUUGGAAGUGCAACUACCCAUCAGCCGCUAGUCGGUCCUUGCUCUACCUGACUGAUUAAAAUUCUUUCUUUAUGGUUGUCAGGAUGACCUAAUAGGUUUAAAAAUGUAGUGUAAGCUUCAAACUCCAGUUGCUGAUGUUUAGUUUGCGCAUCUUAAGGAUUUGGAAGUAUAUGUAUAAUUGGGUUUUGUGAUGUUGCAUAUCUGUCUAGAUCUGUGGACUCCACUAGUUCCAAACUGUAAUUCUUUAUAAGACUGCUGAUUUGACAUUUAGCAGUGACCAUAUGUGGACUGCACUAGAAAUAAUGUGCUUCUUGGAGCUGAAUGGUGUAGCAUUACUAUAUGGCUUUUCUCUCUAGUCUUCAUUGUGUCAUCUGUAGUGAGCUAUAGAGUUUUUUUGUUUCGGGAAUUUUUACAACUUGUUUGCAUGGGUUCACCUAGUAGCAUUGGUUCUUGCUUAUAGUCUUUAAUACACAAUCAGCAAAGCUUACAAUCCACUCAAGAGACUUACUAUUUUGUCACUGUUGAAAAUGGGCUAAAUGAUGUAAAUUGAAUGUGGCUGUCAACUAAAACAAAAUUCAGUAUAGAAUUAGUAUUCAUCCAGUCAUGGACAUACCUGUAGCAUGGUUUUCUCUUGAGACAUAAUAGGCCGUUUCCUACUGUAAAAACUUACAGCCAGCUUCAUACAAUAAAGUAAAUUUUUUCCUGUGUUUUGGCAGGCUCCCGUCAUACAUGUGUAUUGGUGGUGCUGUUACCAAAAUGAUCAUUGUUACUAUGGUGGCAUACAGCUUCAUGGAGCAGAAAGUUUCUACUUGGUAUUUAAUUAAUAAAAUGUUGAGGAAUGGCUGAAACAGUUAAUAAUGAAGUAUUUUUACAUUGCUGGUAUUGUGUUUUCAGCAUAUUGGUAGUUUAUAAUACAGACUUCUUGUUGUCAAAGAUCUUCCCGCUUAAAAAUUAUAUUCCUUUUCUCACGUGUUUAUUAGAGAAGAACAAAUGAUAAAAAUUAGCAUUUUAAUGAUAUAUUUAUGUGUAGAAAUAGGGGGAGAAAAAAAGGCCAACUGAGGUAAUCUAGGUGAAAAAGUUUGUUUUCAGUUUAGCUACAUGGUUUAACCAGAAUUAGAAGAAGAACUUCAUUUCCAACCAAAGAACAGGCCGCACAGCCACCAUUUUGGGGUCUUGAGCAGAGAGAGAAAACAAAUAGGUGGUUUGUGAGAACUCUGAAUUAUGUAGAAAACCAGCUUUUCUACAUAAUAAAUAAGCUUUGCCUUAUUUAUUAAAGUUAGGAUUUCUUUGCAGUUCUUAAAUGUACAUUUAAAUUAUAUCAAGUUGACUUUAGAAGAAAAAAAUUAUAAGCAGCCUACCUCUAUCAUGUAUCUUUGUUGUUAACCAGAGUUUUUAAAAUGAAAAAAAUUUCUGUAAUUUAUUUUUGGUUCUAUGAGAUUAUAAUUAAACCCCAAAUUAUAUAUUUAAAAAACAAAAACCAAAAGAUUUUUAGUCAUUAUUAUAGUAACUGAAAUUAAGUAGAGUUACUUUUUUUUAAAAUUAUUUUUAAAAAUAAUUACUACUUUGGAAAUAAAUUGGCUGGGCAUGGUGGCUCACACCUGUAAUCCCAGCACUUUGGGAGGCUGAGAUGGGAGGAUCACUUGAGCCUUGCAGGUCAAGGAUGCGGUGAGCUGUGACUGUGCUACUGCACCCCAGCCUGGGUGGCAGAGCGAGACCCUGUCUCACAAAAAAAAAAAAAAAAAAAAAAAAAAAAAAGGAACAAAGAAAUUUAAUGUUCAUUGCCCUUGUUCUGUCUAGAUUACCUGUUUGAGCCGUAAGCUACUUGUGCCAACUUGGUGUUGUAAAUAGCAUCCAUGGACCAGUCGUGGUGGCUUAUGCCUGUAAUCUCAACACUUGGGGAAGCCAAGGCAGGCGGAUCACUUGAGGUCAGGAGUUUGAGACCAGCCUGGCCAACGUGGUGAAACCCUGUCUCUACUAAAAAUACAAAAAAAAAAUUGGCUGGAUGUGGUGGUGCGUGUCUGUAGUCCCAGCUACUCAGGAGGUGGAGAUUGUAGUGAGCUGAGAUUGCCGUUACACUCCAGCCUGAGCUACAGAGUGAGACUCCGUCUCAAAAAAAAAAAAAAAAUCCUGGAAUAAUUGGAAUAAUUUGCAAAAAUUACAGUCGUUAACAGAGAGAAUAGAUUGCUUGUUUCCCAAAGACUGGUUAUUGAGUUUCUUGUUCUUUCACAGAGAUAGUUUUGAUCAUUUCAGAGGUAGACAAGUCUGGUUUGUUUUACUUUGUUAUAAAUUAUUUUGGUGUGCCUCCUUGUGUUAGCCGUCAUCCUUAAGCCUAUUGGAUUUUUGACGAGUGUUUAUAAAACCUUUUUUUCUUUUACUGAUAGGAAGGGAGACCAUACUGAAUACUAGCCCUUCCUGCAGAGUCACAGAGCUGCCUUUUUUCCUCCAAAAGCAGGUAGUUUGAAAUGAUAGGAAAGGUCCAGUUUUUCUGUGUUGGUCAUUCAUUUACCCUAGGAGGUUGGUGAGGGGAGGAGAGAUUCUGGGAGAUGUGUCUAUUGUUUCUAUUGCCUUUGUUAUGAUUGGAAGGACUUAGAGUGGCAAGUUAAAUAUUUUAUUAUAGUCCCUGAGAAAGUGGAUUUAAUUAAAGAACAGUUUUAACCUAAAGUUUUAGAAGAGAAAUGCCACUACCAUUUUCUAUCAAUGAUUUUUUUCUGAGAAGGUGACAGCCAUCCUCUUGAGUGGUUUUGUAAAAGUGGUGCUAAUGUGUAUAACCUUAAUUUUUUCUUUUUUUUCUCCCUCUCCCUUUAACAUUUGCUUUUCCUUUCACUGUUGUCAGUCACAACACGCUGCUCUUGAAUCUCUCAGCUGGUCUUGACUCGUGAAUUUACUUAUGCUUUCACUCUUUAAUAAAUACAUUACUUGCAAGCAGUGAAUUGAAAACAAGACAAAAAAAAAAACGACCAUUAGUGAUUGGACAGUUUCUUACUUUGUGUUACAUUUAACUGUUCUUUUGACAGCCCAGUUUUUAAAGCCAGGAUAAUAUUGGACACCGCUUACUCCAGAAACAUGGGUGGAAGCUGGGCCAGGGAUUGGGAAAAUCUCUUCAGGCAUUAUGAUCCUGGACUUGUUGUGGUGAUGGUAAUCUUAGCAGUGGUAAUUUUUUAUUUUCAGACUGAAUUACUCCUUUUGUCAUCAGUGCACCAAUAUGUUAGGCUUACUUUCUCUGUUGUAGCCUUCAUCCUUCUGCUUGGUCUUUUUCAUUUUCCUUUCCUUUCCUUAUGCAACUUGUCUGAUCCUUGUUCAUUAAAGGGUAAUGUUAAGAAGGGAUGUAUCUGUUUGUGUUAGAACUGCCAAUAAAAUCAGUUAAAACAUUAAAUUCUAAUACUGUCAAAAACUUGAUUUCCCCACAAUGUAAUGGGCACUAGCACUUGCUACUGCAAUUUAUAAAUAAAUUAAAACAAACUUUGACUGCCUUAGAAGGCAAAAGUACUAAUGCAGAGUUUAUAAACAGGGGUUUACAGAGGUAAUGAAUUUGUACCAAAACUUUCUUGAUUCUUGCAAAACGAAUUCUGACAGAUCAAAAAAGAUACCAAAAUAAAUUGCUUUGACAUUUCUUUUUAAUUCAUUCAUUGGACUAUUUGUUUUUACCAGUAAAUCCCUGACUGAGACGUUAUGAAAGUGAUAUUGCACCUAGGAAGUCAUUUUUAUAACCUGUCUUUAAUUUGGUCCUUUUGCUAAAGAUUGCAGUCACUGCUUAUUUAUUAUACCAUUGGGCAUAGGGUAGUAAUGCAUUUUCAUUUUGCUUUACUGGCAGUCCUUUGAUUGUAUCUAAAAGAAGGCUGUAUUCUAGAAGUUGUUGUUUUGUUUUUUUUUUUUUUCUGACAUGAGAUGUUCUUUAACAGUUUGGGUUUGGUUUUUUUGUUUUGUUUUUUUACUGUGAUAAUUCUAAUUCUCCCUAUUUAUUGUUUAAAAACAAUAAUAGGAUACAUAAGUAGUUAAACUUAUGAAUUUGUUUUUCAUUCCAUCUUAAAGGCAAAAAUUAAUUCCACAAAUAUAGAGCCACCGAGUACAAGUGGUUGUGGUCGUUUUGAACAUGGUUUCUUCUUUAUUUUGCAGGACCAAAACCAGUCAUGAUCAUGGCAUUUAUUUUUUAAAAAGUUUUUUUUGGGGUUGGGAGGGUAAUGCCUCAGAUUUAGCCUAAGAAAACUCCAUUUUUAGCCCAAAGGUAUAAUAUAUGUAUAUAUAUAUGUGUGUGUGUAUAACAACAACAACAACACAACCAAAAAAACCAAUUGUUUACACCAGCCUGAGUGAAAUGAUGAGGGAAGUAAACAUUGUGUUUUUUCACUAAAGGUGUACAACGGAUAAGGUAAGUCCUCUUUUCAGUGGGCUUACAUCACAAUAAAAAGCGCAGGUUGUGAUGUAAAACAGCUGUGGUAGUAAAGUGCUUGUCUGCCCCAUUUUGCUUUGUUUGGCUGGUUAUGAGUGGAUUAAAUAUAUAUUUAUUAAAAAAAUUAUCCAGCAUAGAUCAAUUAGUUUAAAGUCAAUUUUCUUCGCAACUAGUCCUUUUCACAGCUUACCAGUUACCCUCGCAGCCAGUGUUAAAUCCACUCUAGGAAAUGGGACUUUAGAGCACCAGAUUAAAAGGAAAACUAUUCUUUUCUCUAAGGGCAACUAAUUGUUUCUUUUUAUUUAAACUUUUCACAGCCCCAUUAAAUUGUAAAGCAUCUCCUAGUCUAUGAGGAACAUCAAAAAAAAUUGUAAAGCAUCUUUUGAAAACAAAUUCAACAUACUGAGUUGUAAUUAUAAAGUUUUACUGCAUCAUGUUUAAAAAUGUACUUUUUCUAUUUAACCAUGCCAGUUGAGAUUUUUUUUUUUAAACUAGGUUAAAAAGUUGUGUAGGAGGAUAUCAGUGGGCAGAGUAAAGUGAUACUUGAUGGGAAGUUAUUUGGGGAUCUUAAAAGGAAUUUUUAAAGUUUUACAAUUUAAACCUCCUGAUGCCAUUGCUUAAAAGUGCUUUGCAUUACUUAUUAAUGUAAUUUUGCCAUAGUAAUUUGAAAUUAAUCCCAACUGGACGUCAGCCAAGGUGGUUAAUUGGGUUUAAACUAGGAAAGGAAGGUCUUGAGUGUAAGCUGUGAGAAUGGCUUGUGUUUGGUUCACUGUAGCUUUCUGGUCUCUGCACUCCAAGGCAAGAUCUCUAACCACCCAAAACCCAAUGUGUAAAAUGAGCUGUUGGUUUGGCUUUGCACCUUACCUUGAUUAUGUGUUCCUGUUACAGGGAGAACAGAUCCCAUUCCAAUCGUUGUCAAGUAUGAUGUCAUGGGCAUGGGUCGCAUGGAAAUGGAGCUUGAUUAUGCUGAAGAUGCUACCGAACGGCGCCGUGUCCUAGAAGUAGAAAAAGAAGACACAGAAGAGCUGAGACAAAAGUACAAGGAUUAUGUUGACAAAGAGAAGGCAAUUGCCAAAGCCUUGGAAGACCUCAGAGCCAACUUUUAUUGUGAACUGUGUGAUAAGCAAUAUCAGAAACAUCAGGAAUUUGAUAACCAUAUCAACUCCUAUGAUCAUGCACACAAGCAGAGAUUAAAAGAUCUGAAGCAGAGAGAGUUUGCUCGAAAUGUCUCUUCAAGAUCCCGCAAGGAUGAGAAAAAACAGGAAAAAGCCCUUCGGCGGCUCCAUGAGUUGGCAGAGCAAAGAAAACAAGCUGAAUGUGCACCUGGAAGUGGUCCCAUGUUCAAACCAACCACAGUGGCUGUAGAUGAAGAAGGUGGAGAAGAUGAUAAAGAUGAAUCAGCUACAAAUAGUGGCACAGGUGCCACUGCUUCUUGUGGCCUGGGAUCUGAAUUCUCCACAGAUAAAGGAGGCCCUUUCACUGCAGUACAAAUCACUAAUACCACUGGACUGGCCCAGGCUCCUGGGUUAGCCUCCCAAGGCAUCAGCUUUGGCAUUAAGAAUAAUCUGGGGACCCCAUUGCAAAAAUUGGGAGUGUCAUUUUCUUUUGCCAAAAAGGCUCCUGUCAAACUCGAAUCAAUAGCAUCAGUUUUCAAGGACCAUGCGGAGGAAGGGACCUCUGAAGAUGGAACAAAACCCGAUGAGAAGAGUUCUGACCAAGGACUGCAGAAGGUAGGAGACUCUGAUGGGAGCAGUAAUCUUGAUGGUAAAAAAGAGGAUGAAGACCCUCAGGAUGGAGGGUCCCUUGCCUCAACAUUAUCCAAAUUAAAAAGGAUGAAACGAGAAGAAGGAGCUGGGGCUACAGAGCCUGAGUAUUACCACUACAUCCCCCCAGCACACUGCAAAGUAAAACCUAAUUUUCCCUUUCUACUUUUUAUGAGAGCCAGUGAACAAAUGGAUGGUGAUAAUACUACACACCCAAAGAAUGCCCCAGAGAGUAAAAAAGGCAGUUCUCCCAAGCCUAAAAGCUGCAUCAAGGCGGCAGCAAGCCAAGGAGCAGAAAAGACAGUUAGUGAAGUCUCUGAGCAGCCGAAGGAAACCAGCAUGACCGAGCCCUCAGAACCAGGAAGCAAAGCUGAGGCAAAGAAGGCCUUAGGAGGGGAUGUAAGUGAUCAGAGUUUAGAAAGUCAUAGUCAGAAGGUUUCAGAGACCCAAAUGUGUGAGUCCAACUCUUCUAAAGAAACCUCUCUGGCCACCCCAGCAGGGAAAGAAAGCCAAGAAGGACCCAAACAUCCUACUGGUCCCUUCUUCCCAGUUUUGAGCAAAGAUGAAAGCACUGCCCUCCAGUGGCCAUCAGAACUAUUAAUUUUCACCAAGGCAGAACCCUCCAUUUCAUACAGUUGUAACCCUUUAUAUUUUGACUUUAAACUUUCAAGGAACAAAGAUGCCAGAACUAAAGGAACAGAAAAACCAAAGGAUAUAGGAAGCUCCUCAAAGGACCAUCUCCAAGGCCUAGAUCCUGGUGAGCCAAAUAAAAGCAAGGAAGUGGGCGGAGAGAAAAUAGUACGUUCCUCAGGAGGCAGAAUGGACGCACCUGCUUCAGGGUCUGCCUGUAGCGGCCUGAACAAGCAGGAGCCUGGGGGUAGCCAUGGGUCUGAGACAGAAGACACAGGGAGAAGCCUUCCCAGCAAGAAAGAACGAUCUGGGAAGUCCCACCGGCACAAAAAGAAAAAGAAGCACAAAAAAUCCAGCAAACACAAACGUAAACACAAGGCUGACACAGAAGAGAAAAGCUCUAAGGCAGAGUCAGGGGAGAAAUCUAAGAAGCGCAAGAAACGAAAACGAAAGAAGAAUAAGUCAUCAGCCCCAGCAGAUUCUGAACGAGGACCCAAACCAGAACCCCCUGGGAGUGGCAGUCCCGCACCACCAAGAAGAAGGCGGAGAGCUCAAGAUGACUCCCAGCGGAGAUCCCUCCCAGCUGAAGAGGGGAGCAGUGGCAAAAAGGAUGAAGGUGGGGGUGGUAGCAGCUCCCAAGACCAUGGUGGGAGGAAACACAAAGGUGAACUUCCACCUUCAUCCUGCCAGCGAAGAGCAGGCACCAAACGGAGCAGCCGGUCUAGCCAUCGGAGCCAACCCAGUAGUGGAGAUGAGGAUAGUGAUGAUGCUUCCUCACACCGGCUGCACCAGAAGUCUCCAUCCCAGUACAGUGAGGAAGAAGAAGAGGAAGAUUCAGGCAGUGAGCAUUCCCGCAGCCGCUCAAGGUCUGGCCGGCGCCAUUCCUCGCAUCGUUCCUCCCGGCGUUCUUACUCAAGUAGCUCAGAUGCCUCUUCAGACCAGAGCUGCUAUAGUAGACAGCGCAGUUACUCUGAUGACAGCUACAGUGACUACAGUGACAGAUCACGAAGGCACUCCAAGCGCUCCCAUGACUCAGAUGACUCAGACUAUGCCAGCUCCAAACACCGAUCAAAACGGCACAAAUAUUCAUCUUCUGAUGAUGACUAUAGCCUCAGUUGCAGCCAGUCCCGAAGCCGAUCUCGGAGUCAUACCAGAGAGCGCUCAAGAUCCCGGGGCCGCAGCCGCAGCAGCAGUUGUAGUCGUAGUCGAAGCAAGCGGAGAAGCCGUAGCACCACAGCCCACAGCUGGCAACGGAGCCGGAGCUAUAGCCGGGACCGCAGCCGCAGCACCAGGAGCCCUUCCCAGAGAUCAGGCUCCAGGAAGAGAUCAUGGGGUCACGAGAGCCCUGAGGAGAGGCAUUCUGGGCGUCGGGACUUCAUUCGUUCUAAGAUCUACCGCUCCCAGUCCCCCCACUAUUUCCGAUCAGGCCGGGGAGAAGGUCCUGGGAAGAAAGAUGAUGGCAGAGGAGAUGACAGUAAAGCAACAGGUCCACCUUCCCAGAACAGCAACAUUGGCACAGGAAGAGGGUCAGAAGGUGACUGCAGUCCUGAAGACAAGAACUCUGUCACUGCCAAACUGCUACUGGAGAAGAUCCAGUCAAGGAAAGUGGAGAGGAAACCUAGUGUGAGUGAGGAGGUGCAGGCCACCCCUAAUAAAGCUGGGCCCAAGCUCAAGGACCCCCCACAAGGUUACUUUGGGCCCAAGCUCCCCCCAUCUCUUGGCAAUAAGCCUGUCCUUCCACUGAUAGGGAAGCUCCCAGCUACCCGAAAGCCCAAUAAGAAGUGUGAAGAGUCUGGCUUGGAAAGGGGGGAAGAGCAAGAACAGUCAGAGACAGAAGAGGGGCCCCCAGGGAGUAGUGAUGCCCUAUUUGGGCAUCAGUUCCCUUCAGAGGAAACAACUGGCCCCUUAUUAGACCCACCCCCAGAAGAGUCAAAGUCUGGAGAAGCUACUGCUGAUCACCCUGUGGCUCCACUAGGCACCCCAGCACAUUCUGACUGCUACCCUGGGGACCCAACCAUCUCCCAUAACUACCUCCCCGACCCCAGUGAUGGGGACACCCUGGAGUCCCUGGAUAGCAGCAGUCAGCCAGGCCCUGUGGAGUCCAGCUUGCUGCCUAUAGCACCAGACCUUGAGCAUUUCCCCAGUUAUGCACCUCCCAGUGGGGAUCCUAGUAUUGAGUCAACAGAUGGGGCUGAGGAUGCUUCACUGGCCCCCCUGGAAAGCCAGCCCAUCACCUUCACCCCUGAGGAGAUGGAGAAGUACAGCAAGCUCCAGCAGGCUGCUCAGCAACACAUCCAGCAGCAGCUUCUGGCCAAGCAAGUAAAGGCCUUUCCAGCCUCAGCUGCCCUGGCCCCAGCCACACCAGCCCUGCAACCCAUCCACAUUCAGCAGCCAGCUACAGCCUCUGCCACCUCCAUCACAACUGUUCAGCAUGCCAUCCUACAACAUCAUGCUGCCGCAGCUGCUGCCGCCAUCGGCAUUCACCCUCACCCCCAUCCCCAACCACUUGCCCAGGUGCAUCAUAUUCCCCAGCCCCAUCUGACCCCCAUUUCUUUGUCCCACCUCACUCACUCAAUCAUCCCUGGCCACCCUGCCACCUUUCUCGCUAGCCAUCCCAUCCACAUCAUUCCCGCCUCAGCCAUCCAUCCUGGGCCCUUCACCUUUCACCCUGUCCCACAUGCUGCCCUCUACCCCACCCUACUUGCUCCACGGCCUGCUGCAGCAGCUGCCACUGCACUUCACCUUCACCCACUACUUCACCCCAUCUUCUCAGGUCAGGACCUGCAACAUCCCCCCAGCCAUGGCACGUGAGUUGGGGGAUGGGAUCCUAGGUAGGGCCAGGGGAGGAGACCCAUAAAUGUUCCCUUGGGGGUGUUGAGCCAUUAAUACCAGCAAGUAGAAGCUGGGAUGGGCAGUGUCUGACAGCCAAAGAAUUGAGUUUUGGCUUGCAGGGGUGGGUUUAGAUUUGAAGUUUGCUUUCAGUUUACUAUCAGGGAUUUCUUUUUCCUGUCCUCCUCUCAAUUUGUCCCUCCCUCUUCUGUGUUUCUAAGCUAGGGAACACCAGUAAGUGCUACCCACCCCUCUGCAGCAACAUCUCCAAACUGUCAAGUUUAGAUAAUCCCCUCCUCCCUCUGCUUUUUUCCUCUGCUCUUCCCUUCUGUAAAUUUUAAAACAUUUUCCUCCCCUCUGGCCAGUGGGUUGUCACCAGAGCACUUGCUGUGGGCCCAUCUGGUCUUGCCUUCUCAGCGCCACAGGGAAGGCCAAGCUGUUCUAGUGGUGGAAGUGCCACCAUUUUGGGGUAGUAUCUUUGACCAUCUUUGGUGACGUUACGUUAUCCCAGGUGAGGUGGAAAGCGUCUCACCUGGAACCUGAUAUAACUCAGGCUGCAAUUCCAUCCAGUUCCCACAUCAACGGAGCCACACAUUUGGCACUGUUAUCUUGGUAUCCCUCAUCCCAGAAGAGGCAUCUCCAUAUCCCAGAAAAGAAGAUCCUAUCAUGAAUAAAAGCUGUAUGGCCCAGAGAGGAGCUCAUGUGUCUAAAGUGAAGGGUAUAUUUUCUUCUGUUGUGUUGAUGUUUCCUUCUUAAUUUAUAGGAUUUUUUUAAUGUAAAAAAUUGCACUGAACUCUAUAAACGUAAAUGCUGCUUUUUGUAGCUCAUAUAAAAAAGGUUCCAUAUUUGUAGUAUACUGCAAUAAUAUUUUUUACAUCCAGCUCUUUAAGUGAUCCUCGUUCUGGUGGCUUUGUGUAAAUAUGUUUGCCCUAGUUGAAUUAAGAAACUCUAAAGGUUAUAAAAUGAAAACAAAAAAUAAAAUAUUUGUUUUCUGCUAGAUGCAAAACUGACUAAGCAUGUAUAUUUUACCAAACUUAUGUAUUUUUUGAAGUUAUGAACUAUAAAAUGUUAAAACAUUUUUUGCUGGGACAAAAUGUUAAGUAAUUUGCAGUAUGUAGUGCCCCCAGUAUUGGGAUUUUUGAGCUAAUGGGCAGCAGUCAGCUGGGGGCUUCUGAGGGAUGCUCAUCUUUAACAGUCUCCCUCAUGUACUUUUGCUGUUUUACACAGAGAAACAGGUAGACCCCACAGAGGAGAAGGAGGGGAUUCAACAGCUUUAUUGUCUGGAAGCAGUGAGAUUUGGUGAUUGUCUGGGGGGAUUCCUGGGUUUCCCUGGGUACCUUGUUCCAGGCAGUCAGUCCAUUUGCCUUCCUAGUACUUAGCCCCCUCUGACAAUUUUUUUUUUAAUGUGCCUUUUGGGUUGGUAGAAACGGAAGUAGAAGUAGGCUGGAGGAUGAGUUGGGACAGUCUUCCUUUUGUUGGGAGGUGAGCACAUUUACAGAUAUUUUGCUUCAUAGUUUCCAUGCCCUCUGCCCAGCUCAGUUUAGACAGUAAACGUUCCUUGUUUCUUUUCUCCCAUGACACUGACAAGAGGAAUUACCACCUCAGCCUCUUUUGCCCCUCUUCUUGCCUUUCACCCAGGCUCUCAGCCCUAAUUAACACACUGACCCAAAGGUGCUUGUGUUGCAGGUCCCAUCUCCUUUGAUGAGGUUAACAAUUCCCACUUUGGCAUUUUCCUAACUAUUCGUGUGGCUAGAAUUGGUUGGUUGGUCACUUGACAAGAAAAACCAUACUUACCUGGGCCAAGGCUCUGUUCCUGCCUUCGCAAAUUCUCAAAAGAGUAAAGUUUAUGAAAAGAAAGUGGCAGGCAAACACAACUCUUGACUGCCCUCCCACCCUCCUACCUGUUCAGUACUCAUCUGAUUCAGAAGCAUCACUUCUUGGAUAACUAGCACUGGAAAAAUGAAAUCAUCUGUGUAAGUGAAGGGACUCAUUUUUCUUUGCUUUCAGCCCAUGUAAAUAAAUAAUACAGUAUUAACAUUUUCGUGCUGCUUCCCAUUAGCUUGUAGAUUGAGCCAUACUCUGGCUGCCUCUUUGCCUUCCUAGGGGCAUUUUCUUUAACUUCCAGAAUAGUGAUUUUAAAAGUAAAAAUAAAAAUAAACCUUACUUACAAGCAUAACAGAUUGUAUUUAACUUUAUCACAUAUGAUAGAGAUAUAUAUGCUGUAAAAUGAGGGAAAGGAACUUUCUAAUAAACCAAUGAUUUGUGGAAA